GUUGUCUUGGAGAGGGACGCGUAGGCUACGCCACCGCGGACGGGUCGGAUCCGGUCCCUGGACGCGGAACAGAGAUCCCCUGAUUCAGCCACCCCCAGACUGAGCCCCGUAGAGUGCGUUCUUACCUUCCUGCCCCGACGAAGGUCCCAGAGACGCUGCGGACAACACCAGCAUGUCGAGCGAGCAGAGCGCGCCGGGGGCCUCACCCAGGGCCCCGCGUCCGGGGACCCAGAAGUCUUCUGGCGCGGUGACCAAAAAGGGAGAGCGCGCGGCCAAAGAGAAGCCAGCGACCGUUCUGCCUCCCGUGGGGGAGGAGGAGCCCAAAAGCCCUGUGAUAGAACCCCAAUCAAACUAAGCAUGAAGGGGAAAUGUAUCCGAAGUCUUCUUGAUACAAAUCUGCCAGCUUCGUCAUCACGGGGACAAGAACUUGCUGUCUCUGGAAUCGAAGUAAAACAACUUGGGAAAAAGAUCUGAUCAUCCAGCAUUAGCCAGGUACUAUCUCUUUGUCAGUGCUGGUGGAUGGGGAGAAGGAAUUAUAGGAGCUGGAGAAACAACAUCUUCUGGAAGGGAAGACAAGACAGUAUACAAUCCCCUACAGAGGAGUACCAGUGCUCCGGGGUCCUCGAGACCGACUUCGCCGAGCUCUGCACGCGGUGGGGCUACACGGACUUCCCCAAAGUUGUCAACCGGCCCCGCCCCCACCCGCCCUUCGUCCCCUCCGCCUCUUUGUCGGAAAAGGCCACCUUAGACGAUCCGCGGCUGUCGGGGUCCUGCAGCCUCAAUAGCCUGGAGAGCAAAUACGUGUUCUUCCGGCCCACCAUCCAGGUGGAGCUGGAGCAGGAGGACAGCAAGUCAGUGAAGGAAAUCUACAUCCGCGGUUGGAAGGUUGAGGAACGGAUUCUGGGUGUCUUCUCUAAAUGUCUGCCCCCGCUUACCCAGCUACAGGCCAUCAACUUGUGGAAGGUGGGGCUGACCGAUAAGACCCUGACCACCUUCAUCGAGCUCCUGCCUCUCUGUUCAUCCACGCUCAGGAAGGUGUCUCUGGAGGGGAACCCACUGCCGGAGCAGUCCUAUCACAAGCUCAUGGCCUUGGACAGCACGAUUGCGCACUUGUCUCUGCGGAACAAUAACAUCGACGACCGCGGGGCGCAACUCCUGGGCCAGGCGCUGUCCACGCUGCACAGCUGCAACCGGACCCUCGUCUCGCUCAACCUGGGUUUCAACCACAUCGGUGACGAGGGCGCAGGCUACAUCGCGGACGGCCUCCGGCUGAACCGUUCCCUGCUCUGGCUGUCCCUGGCCCACAACCGCAUCCAGGACAAGGGCGCCCUGAAGCUGGCUGAGGUCCUGCGCGCCUUCGAGCUGACACACACCGAAGUGGUGGAGCGCCGACGCCUCCUGCUGGAAAAAGGGACACAGGAGCGCUCGCGAUCGCCCUCCUCCUCUCGACACGGGGACUCCAAAACGGACCGUGAGAAGAGUCAGAUGGUAGGGAUCAGCAAUAGUGCAUUGGUGGACAAGACAGACAAGACGCAGACAAUGAAAACCCCUAAGGGCCUGGGCAAGAAAAAGGAGAAAUCAUGGGAAUUGGCCAAGAAAGAGGAGAAGUUGGGGUCUGGGCAGUCACCCACACAAGGAACCCCUAAGAAGGAAGAUGCCACAAAGGCAGGCAAGGGGAAGGUAACCAUCCCUGAACAGAAGCCAAGCAGGGCAAAAGGGAUCAAGAUCGGGAGCAGAGAGAAGCGCAGCAUCCUCCUGGAGUCCGAGCAGCUGGUUGUUGAGGCUACUGAGGUGGUCAACCCUCUCCUGGAGCCUGUGGAGCACCGAGAUGGGAAAGUUUUCAUGCCUGGGAACAAGGUCCUUUUGCACCUCAACCUCAUCCGGAACCGCAUCACAGAGGUGGGGCUGGAGGGCUUCCUCGCCACGGUGCAGUAUCAGAUGCAGUUCUCCAAGGCCAAGAGUGCAUCCAAGGGUCCAGUGGGGCUGCUGUGGCUGUCCCUGGCUAAAAAUUGCUUCGCCCCACAAUGUCCUGCGUACGCCAUAAUCCAGGAGCUGAUGUUGCCAAGGGAUCCCAUCAAGGCCAAACUCAGGGAGGAUGAGGCCAUGGCAUUCUUCCCCUAGCCCCCUCCCACCUGCUUGCCUCUAAGACUCGGGGCUACAGAAGCACCUCCUGUCCCUGUGUGGGGUGACCUCCCUGGGGGAGAUCUCAGACCAAUAACAAAGUCUGUUGCUAUACUUUUCCUUGA